GACUUCCGGCUACGCCGUUGUCUGGGUGGCGCGGUCGAGUCAUCGCAGGGCCUCACCGCUUCGUUCUCCCGUCCCUCCCCGCGCCUUGGCGCGGGGGGUCGACUAGCCAAGUGAGGCGGGAGGCGACUCGGACCUUUCCCUGCAUUUCGUUUCGGCCAGUGCCGGGGGCUACCCGCCCUGGGGCCUGGGAUCCUUGGGGCCCGUGAGGCCCACUCUUAGCGGCCGGGGCCUACCGCGGCCCGCCGCUGGCCCUCAUGAGGCAUAGCCUGACCAAGCUGCUGGCAGCCUCGGGCAGCAACUCCCCAACCCGCAGUGAGAGCCCGGAGCCGGCUGCAACUUGUUCGCUGCCCUCUGACCUGACCCGGGCUGCAGCGGGGGAGGAGGAGACGGCGGCGGCCGGAUCUCCCGGCCGCAAGCAGCAGUUUGGCGACGAAGGAGAGUUGGAAGCCGGGAGGGGGAGCCGCGGCGGCGUGGCCGUGCGCGCGCCCUCCCCCGAGGAGAUGGAGGAGGAGGCGAUCGCCAGCCUCCCGGGGGAAGAGACGGAGGAUAUGGACUUUCUGUCUGGGCUGGAACUGGCGGAUCUCCUGGACCCCAGGCAACCGGACUGGCACCUGGACCCCGGGCUUAGCUCGCCGGGGCCUCUCUCCUCGUCUGGCGGAGGCUCGGAUAGCGGCGGCCUGUGGAGAGGGGACGAUGACGAUGAGGCCGCGGCUGCUGAAAUGCAGCGCUUCUCUGACCUGCUGCAAAGGCUGUUAAACGGUAUCGGAGGCUGCAGCAGCAGCAGUGACAGUGGCAGCGCCGAAAAGAGGCGGAGAAAGUCCCCAGGAGGAGGCGGCGGUGGCGGCAGCGGUAACGACAACAACCAGGCGGCGACAAAGAGUCCCCGGAAGGCGGCGGCGGCCGCUGCCCGCCUUAAUCGACUGAAGAAGAAGGAGUACGUGAUGGGGCUGGAGAGUCGAGUCCGGGGUCUGGCAGCCGAGAACCAGGAGCUGCGGGCCGAGAAUCGGGAGCUGGGCAAACGCGUACAGGCACUGCAGGAGGAGAGUCGCUACCUACGGGCAGUCUUAGCCAACGAGACUGGACUGGCUCGCUUGCUGAGCCGGCUGAGCGGCGUGGGACUGCGGCUGACCACCUCGCUCUUCAGAGACUCGCCCGCCGGUGACCACGACUACGCUCUGCCGGUGGGAAAGCAGAAGCAGGACCUGCUGGAAGAGGACGACUCGGCGGGAGGAGUCUGUCUCCAUGUGGACAAGGAUAAGGUGUCGGUGGAGUUCUGCUCGGCGUGCGCCCGGAAGGCGUCGUCUUCUCUUAAAAUGUAGGGUCAAGUAAUCUGCUCUUUAUCCGCGUUUACCCCUUUCAACUCCCUUACACCAUGUCAAACUUACCUUAGUGGGACAUCUUCACCGGACACAUUUCAGAGGAGAGAAAAAAAGUAAUAUUGAAUCUUAAAGUGUUUAGCUAAAAGCAUGAAUGUGACACAGUAACCAACUCCUAAUGAUAACAUGUGACUAUUAAAUCUCUCUGACAGUUUCUUUUUUAGGUGAUUUCCUUCCUGCCAGGCUCCGUUGUAGGGGUUACAGAACAGUCGUUCCCGCCUCACAACCUGGUAAGGAUCCAUCUCUUCCCGUAACGCUCAUGCUCUGCUGCUUUGUCUACUUUAAUGGGCAACAUCUCAGUUUGUGUGUGUGUGAUUUUUUUUUUUUUUUCUGUUUUGGAAGGUGGGAGGGAAAUCUAAUUUGGGCCCUGUCCACCCUGGAAACAGACUUGUGCUGGUCAAGAAUGUAUUUAAGAUGCCUCUUCUGGUUGAAAUAGCUAUUAAUGUGUCCCCUUAUUCAGACUUGCGUGUACCUAGCUCUUCUGUCCCCAGUGUGGACAUGGCCUUGGAUGACAUCGGUUCCAACUGUACACUGAAACCUGCUUAUAGAGAGACAGUUUGGAGACAGUGAAACAGGUGAAGUUGAAUGGAAGUUCCGAGUUGUACAAGGUGCAAAUUGGAAUUCCGAUUUUAGGGCAACUUUUCAGAGGUUGACAGUUAAGUAUUUGGGGCAUGCACAAAUGUGAUAGUUAUUUUGCUGGAGGUGACAGGUAUCUCUUAAAUAUCAACAAUGCCUUUUAGUUUUCAGUAUGAGAUAUAGAAACAGUCUAUAAUGGAGUAACAUUUUAAUGUCUCACCAUUAGAGAAGUUGGAAAUUAACAUACAUAUGAGACUCCUGCGUUUUAGUUAAUUGGAGAAUAAGAAUGGCUAAUGUUUCUUUGAGGACCAGCAGUGAUUACCCUAUCACUGAGAUUGAAUAAAUUGUUGAACAUCUUUAUUUUUGUUGUAUUAAAAUUUUAGGUUAAAUUUAUAUAUGUAUGAUUAGAUAUUGAAGGUUGUGAAAUGUGAAUGAAAACGUGUAAAGUGAGGCUUCACAAAGAAUCUUAUUCUCUGUGUUUCAAAAGUAUUUGUCCUAUUUUAAAAUAAUUUUUUAAAUUGAGUGGUUCUGGCCACUUAAAUGACACGAUUGGUACUAUUUUCCUAAGGUGGGAUUUAUUCCCUUGAAUCUAUUAACCAGUUGUAUAAAUUGAAUUAUGGUGUCCUUCAGUGUAAGAGGCAUUAAGAAAUUCUUUGUGAAACAUCACUGCUUGAUAAAGUAUAUACGUAUUUAGCAUCCUUGUUUUUCUUUGUGCUAAAGUGGAUACAGCUGUUGGGGCAGAAGAGACGGGACCAGCUGCUGGCCACAUUUCCUGCUUUAUUUUAAAAGGUAGUAUAAGAAAUGAGGAAAAAGAGGUAAUAUCAGGGCUUCUGCUGUUUUUUAUUUUUAACAUGUUCAUAAUUAAAAAGUAUUUUCCAGCAGUCCAAAGAUGUAAGUUAUCUUACACAUAAAAUGUUUUAUUUUGUUAUUUGGUUAUGAAAAUGGAAUCCUUGUUCUUGCACAACUGUAAAUGUUUUGUUGCUAGAUAAUACGAUUUGAGACCUGAAUUGGUCUUUGGUUUCCAGUGCAUCACAGCAUAUUUUGUAAAAUCAUCUACUACUGCACUUGAGCAUGAAUGGGUAGUAGCCAAACUCACAAAUUGGAGUGAUGAACCUGCUUAUACCUAAGGGCAGGAGCAAGCCCCUCACAAUGCAGCUGCAUGGGUUUUUAGUGCCUACUGAAUUAUAUAUAUAUAUACAUAUAUAUAUAUAUAUAUAAACCAAAAGUAGUUGGAAAGAUUAUUUGAAAUGACUAAUUUGUGCUAUCUUUAUGAAAUAUGUUAAAUGUAGCUUUUUUGAAACAGAAGCCUUGAAUUGAAAUUUAACUAAUACUUGAACAUUUUGUAUAUAUUUCUUUGUAUAUAAUUUUGUGCAGUACCAAUGACAAAAAUAUGGUGUCAUAAUAAAACCAGGUUUGUUGAUCUUUUAGUUAUGGGCUCAAAGAAUUUAUUCAUCUCUAACAUGAUAUUGGAAAAUAAUGGAUGAAAAUAGGAAAAAUGAUUGUUAAUGCUGACUGUGGGUCUUAAAAGGUUCUGGAAAGCAGUAAGUUCAUUUUUCUAAAAACUAUAACAUUCUGUUGGAGUAUUUUCUUCCUUACGUCAAUACUUUUCCUGCAUUAUUUGAAAUUGUGGGCUGGGGAGAAACAGUAGUCAAAGCUUUCUGAAUUGAGAUACUUUGAAAUUCCAAGUGUAGAUUUUUAGAAUGUCAUUUUAUAAAUGGCAGUUUUUGGAAUUACUUGAUAAGAACUUUUGAAAAUGGAAGGAUUAGUAUGGCCUAUUUUUAAAGCUGCUUUGUUAGGUUCCUUAUGUUUUAUUAACUGUCUUUUCUCAGUUUCCAUUUCAUUUUUUUUUUUCUAGUUUUGGUGACUUAGUGAUUUUGUCAUUUUUUACAUCAACUUCAUGGUCUUGUUUUUACAUGGUAAUUGCAUGUACUUAGGAUCUAUCUAAUAGGGGCUUUAAAUAAAUUUGGUCAUAUUUAUGUGUAAGCACAUUUUACUGUAAAUGUUUGGGUUUCUGAAUUUAAACAGAUCUGUUUAUUUCAGUAUGUAGUAAACAAUAUCUUAAAGUGUCCGAUUCACUACUUGUUAAUUAAAAAAGUUAUGAUUAAUGUGAAACUGUUGUCUUACUAUUUUUAGAAAAUUGUGUUCUGGAUGAUUAGCACAUGGAUAAAGGAGAUUUCUGGAAUAUAAAAUGGAUUGUUUUUGAAAUUUCUAGGUUUGGCUCUAUUUACUGUAAUGGUUGAAAACAAUUUAGUAUUUGGGUGACCCUUUUGUUUUUCUUCUAAAUGUGCCUCUGGUAAAAUACAGAACUAGACUAAAGAUGUAGCUUUUUAAUAUUUGUCUUUUGAUGGUGGCAGGAGUUCAUACAUUAAUUGAACUAACACAUCAUAUUUUGACCUACUAUUUCUAUCAUAUUGACUUACUGUUUCUGCACUUCUUUGACCAGACUUAUCUUAAAAAGUCCACUUUUGUUAAAAUGUAGUCACACCUCUGAUAUAAUCCAACAAGAAGUGUUCAAAAUAUUUUAAAUAUUUGUGCAUUUUAUAAUCACUAAAUUAAUCUCUCUCUCUUCUCUUUGAACAGCUUAGCAGUGUCUGCAAAAACGAAUCUUUUCCUACAACCUGUUAACUGACUGGACUGUUGGUAACAAAGUAAUUGUGAGAACCAUGUCGGUCAAAAAUUUGGCAUCUGCUGAAAAAAAUGAAUGCCAUUUUCAAGUUCCCAAAUUACUUCUAUACUGAUUUCACUUUCCAGAAAUGGAGAUAUGAAAAGAUUCUCUGGAAUCCUUGAAAGACUUAAUAGAGAUACAUGAGACUAAGUUAAUCUUGGAACAAAAUUAUACUUUUUUUGUCUUUCAUGGGAGUGAUACUCAGUUAUUGCAUAUCUUUACAAAAUUGUAACCUUUGGAGAAUUACAGUAUUUCAUCAAGAAAUUAGAGUUUUUACAUAAUCAAGAGCAUAUUCUAUGGAAUUAACAUUUAGUGGACUAGAAUUACAUAAGCAGGCCAUCAGUGAUCACAAGGCAUAUGAGUUUGUAUUUAUUUCCUGGAACAUGAGAGCUAAUUUGGAGUACAGACAGACACCCUGCUGAGUAGAAUAUAAAAGUUAAUGUAAAGUUCUGAACUAUAAAGAGUAGUCCUUUUAAAUAGAUGCAUUGAUUUGUAUAUCUUUGAAAAAGUUGAUUAUGAUUAAAUGUGUGGGUAGUUAAUUACAAUUUAGGGUAACAACCAGGAUGUAUGGAUUCUUGAGGUUUUGGCUUCUUGAGCUUUCUCUUGAGUACUUGAUACUGUUUUCUGAAUAUUUUGAGGUUUCUAAUUAAUGGUAUGCUAGUUUCUACUGUUUUAUAUAAAAAUUUAUCUAGUGUUGUAUAAGGACUUUAGUAUUGUGGAUGAUGGGAGUGGCUUUUUGUGGCAUAUGGUUGUUUUAAUUGAAAUAUUUUUUCAGUUUAUUACAAGUGUGAAAAAACACUCAAAACUCUGGAUUGUUUUAUUUCAUUUUUGUUGGAUUAUGUUAAUACAUUCCUUCACGUGGUUUAGAUUGAGUCAUUUUAUCUCACUUACUUGGAAAUGUGCAGCUGAUAGAAGAGGGAUUGGGUAGGAGAUUGGCUUUUACUUCAUAAUAAAUAUACAGUUGGUUAUUGUAUUAUUCAAAACUUAUUAAAUCCAUUCAGUUUCUUACCAUUUUAAGUGUAUUCAGUGCCUGUGAAGCCAGGCAGCAGAGUAUUCCCACUGGCUUAAAACUUAGGCGCUGAUGCUCCUACAGUACAGCUAGUUAUAAUUCCAGAACCAAAGGCACCAACAUUAUUUGGUGACCUUAACUACUACUUUGAUAGAACAGACUGGGUAAUUCACUGAUAAUGAGUCAUUACCUUUUUAAUAUGUGAUUAUCUAGUUCAGCAUUUUGAAUGUGUAGUUUAAGGUCUGAUUUAGUAAAAUUUUAAAGCUAAAUAAUCUGAUGACUCUUGAAAGUUUAAUUGGUAGUAUGACAUUUAUGUUUUUUUCCCCCAGACUCACAGCCAAUACAAAGUUUUGAGACUCCUAAAUGUUAAUAUUUUUGCUGUUUUUCUGAGCUGUUUUUUUAUUUACUUACCACCUAAGCUGCGGAUCAAAAAGGGAAUUCUUCCAUUAGAAAUUUGUAGUGUUGUGUGGCCAGCACAGUAUUUUUCAGAUUUGAAUUUCAGUACCUCUGUGUAGCCUCAGUACUCUCAACACCAGUCACUCUUUAUUGUCUUAAAAUAUUCCAUACUUUUUGUUGACCCAAAAUUGUUGAAAAUAUUUUGCUCAGUUUUCACAAUGAACUAAUUGAAAAGUGUAGUUACUGUGUUGUAAACAUUUGUGUAGUUCUGUUAAUACACUGAUUUGAAUUUUAUUUAUCUCAACUUCCUUUAGCGUCUGCCUCCAAAUUUUGUCUUUGCUGUAUACCCACUGAGAUCAAUUCCCUAGACCCCUCUGGCUCUUAGUGUACUAUAAUUUGGGCUUUAUAAAAUAUAUUGUCUUAAUUUAAAUAGAAUGUGAGCCCUCUUUUUUUUUUUUUAAGCCAAAUAACUACACAAAGUAAAUUAUAAAAGAUUUAAAUAGUUUGUCUACAGUGACUAGACUGAAAUAUAAAAAUUGAUUGAGGGUAGUUUACUUCAGGUGUUAGCUACAAAUGACUAAAUGUCCUUAAAUAAUGCAGAUAUCUGCCCUCUGAACAAAAAUUUUGGCAAAGUAAAUUUGUAGCAACAGACUUAACAUGAUUUAUUGCUUAUGUUGCCCAUUUCUGCUAAUGGAAAAGAUAAUUUAAAAAUAUGUGGCAGAGGACAGAUAUUAGAAAUACUUUUUGGUUACAGAAACCAUUGUAAACUCAUCCUCAUUUAUAAAUGGUAUUAUGCUAGGGAGUAAUUGGACUAGGAAUGUUUAAAGAUAAGUAAGGAAACAAUGUGUGCUCAAUCGUCAAAGAACUUAGUUAUAUCAUUGGGCUUUGAAUUAUCUAAGUUGAUUACAUAAUUCUAUAUUCUUAAGGAGUCUUAACUCGGUACUUGGGUUAACGCCAGAAAUUACUUUUAAUUCAUUGUUUUUUUCACUGGGAUGAGUAGAACUCUGCUUUUAGUAAAAGUGACAGAAUAUAGGUAAAAUGGAUGAUUUGGGAUCAGAGCUUUUCAUCUUGAUAUUUUAGCCUGUAAAAUAAACAGCUAUAUUGUUUUGCCCUUUAAA